CCACAGAGCGAGGCCCUACCUCUUAAAAAAAAGAAAACACACACAAACCAAAAGAAAAUGUUAAUAUCAAUAAAUGUUUCAGUCAAAUCUUGGCCUAGGGCUGUUUUAUAUUUUUAAAGUAACUUUGCAUGUGUUUUAUACAAGUCUUAGUGUGGAGUAACUCAUUUUGCACCCACAUGCUACCUAAAGCAUAUAGUCAUGCACCACAUAACAUUUUGGUCACGGAUGGACUACAUAUGUGAUGGUGGUGCCAUAAGGUUAUAAUAUGGUAUUUUUAGUGUACCUUUUCUAUGUUUUGCUAUGUUUACAUACACAAAUACUUACCAUUGUGUUACAGUUGCCUAUAGUAUUCAGUGCAGUCACAUGCUGUACGGAUUUGUAACUUAGGAGCAAUAUGCUAUACCAUAGAGUGUAGGUGGGUGGUAGGCUAUACCAUCUCGGUUUGUGUAGGUGUACUCUAUGAUUGCACAAUGAUGAAAUUGCCUAAUGACAUAUGUCUUAAGAAGGUAUCCCUGUUAAGCAUAUAUCCUAUUCAUGACUUUUCUUUCUUUAGUCCCUCACCUGCUUCUCACUUGCCUUGUAUUUGAGCAUUUAUUGACAUAUAGAUGAACCUGAUAUGAAUGAAUAUAUUAUUCAUUAUAUUAAGCUAGUAGUGUUCUAAGUAUGCUAGGUAUUAUUCCCUAUGGUGUGCCAGAACUGUGAUGGCAUUGGUCUUAUCCUUGAUAAAUAAUGAAUUCCUGGUAGCUAUGUAUAUGGCCAAUGCUCACAACUUUUUUUUUUUUUUUGGAAUCUCCUAUGUCUACUUCUUUCUACACAGACACAGUAACAAUCUGAUCUCUCUUUCUUUUCCCCACAUUUCCCCCUUUUCUUUUCGACAAAACUGCCAUCGUCAUCAUGGCCCGUUCUCGAUGGUUGCUGUCUCUUCAGAGCUGUUGGGUACACCUGCAGAAAGGCUGUCACUUCACACUUGGAAGAUUGCACAGCGGCCAGGCAGAGGUGCUCCUCACCUCCCAGACGGGGCGGCUGGGCAGAGGCGCUCCUCACUUCCCAGAUGGGGUGGCGGCCGGGCAGAGGUGCUCCUCACCUCUCAGACGGGUUGGCGGCCGGGUAGAGGAGCUCCCCACCUCCCAGACGAUGGGCGGCCGGGCAGAGGCGCUCCCCACCUCCCAGACAAUGGGCGGCCGGGCAGAGGUGCUCCUCACCUCCCAGACGGGGCGGCCGGGCAGAGGCGCUCCUCACUUCCCAGACGGGGUGGUGGCCGGGCAGAGGUGCUCCUCACAUCCCAGACGGGGUGGUGGCUGGGCAGAGGCGCUCUUCACAUCCCAGACGGGGCGGCCAGGCAGAGGCACUCCUCACAUCCCAGACGGGGCGGCCGGGCAGAGGCGCUCCUCACCUCCCAGACGGGGCAUCCGGGCAGAGGCGCUCCUCACUUCCCAGACGGGGCGGCCAGGCAGAGACGCUCCUCACAUCCCAGACGGGUUGGUGGCCGGGCAGAGGCACUUCUCACUUCCCAGACGGGGUGGCGGCCGGGCAGAGGCACUCCUCACUUCCUAGACAGGGUGGUGGCCGGGCAGAGACACUCCUCACCUCCCAGACGGGGUGGCGGCCGGGCAGAGGCGCUCCUCACCUCCCAGACAGGGCGACCGGGCAGAGGCGCUCCUCACUUCCCAGACGGGGUGGCCGGGCAGCAGCGCUCCUCACAUCCCAGAUGGGGCGGCCAGGCAGAGAUGCUCCUCACUUCCUAGAUGGGGUGGCGGCCGGGAAGAGGCGCUCCUCACUUCCCAGACGGGGCGGCCGGGCAGAGGGGCUUCUCACAUCCCAGACGAUGGGCGGCCAGGCAGAGAUGUUCCUCACUUCCUAGAUGGGGUGGCAGCCGGGCAGAGGCUGUAAUCUUAGCACUUUGGGAGGACAAGGCAGGCGGCUGGGAGGUGGAGGUUGUAGUGAGCCGAGAUCACGCCACUGCACUCCAGCCUGGGCAACAUUGAGCAUUGAGUGAGCGAGACUCCAUCUGCAAUCCCAGCACCUCGGGAGGCCGAGGCGGGCAGAUCACUCGAAGUCAGGAGCUGGAGACCAGCCCGGCCAACAAGGCGAAACCCCGUCUCCACCAAAAAUACAAAAACCAGUCAGGCGUGGCGGCACGUGCCUGCAAUCCCAGGCACUCGGCAGGCCGAGGCAGGAGAAUCACGGGAGCCCGAGGCAGGGAGGUUGCAGUGAGCCGAGAUCACGGCAGUACAGUCCAGCCUCGGCAACAGAGGGAGACCGAAGAAAAAGAAAGAAAGAGAGAGAGAGAGAAAGAGAGAGAGAGAAAGAGAAAGAAGGAAAGAAAGAAGGAAAGAAAGAAGGAAAGAAGGAAAGAAAGAAAGAAGGAAAGAAAGAAGGAAAGAAGGAAGGAAGGAAGGCAGGCAGGUCACAAAUAUUUGUUGAGUUAAAUUUUUAGCAUUACUAGCUUGUUGUCACUGUCUUCAGCUGCAGAAAAAAUGCUGGACACAAAGCUGAAGCAUGGUGCAACAGUCAGUUUUACUGUAGUCUGGGGAAAAGUCUGCCUUCAGACCAGGAUCUGUCUGUCCCCUCUGGCCCAAGUCUGCAUAGGCCACCAUGGCUGCAGUGACAAGAGGGGACUAGGGAGACAGUACCCUCUUGAGGGGACCUCUAAGGUUGGGGAAAUCUCCCUACACUCGGAGACAGUGGGGGGAAGAUGAGAAGCGGGGGAAGUGAGGUGAGAGUGGAAAGGGGAGAUGAGAGGGAAAGAAAGCACAGAGGUGGAAAGGUGGAGGAGAAACAACCUGUGACGGAUGAGGCACUGUAAAGGGGCAGGGGUUACUCCUCAGCCAGCUCAGUUGGGCCCCAGUAACCUGGUGAAGAAGGAAAAGUGACAAAAAGAAGGCUGGAGAAUAAUCACAUACCUUUCCAAGAACCUAUUUUCUAUCUUUCCCUGCUCCCAGUCCCUAGUCAUUUAUCAGUGACACAUCACCCAUUGUUAGGAGUGUCUGUAGCCUCUAGAUCUGCUUGAAAAAGCAUCAUGAAGUACAGAAACUCAGGUUCCCUCUAGAUGACACAGCUUCUGAAGCAGACUUCUGCUCUGGGUUCUCCUGGCUAACAUGUCUGGCUCUCAUUCUCCAGAAGAAUUCUGUUCAGCAGAAUCUCAGUGGUGGGGUUUUGAGCUGCUGGAAGCAGCAUCCCAAGGUCCCUGACACCAAUCACAUUUUACCAAUGCAUUUCUCUAACCAUUUCUUUCCAAGUCUACAACCAUCCUAAUCUAUGACAUUGAAUCGUCUCAUCUGAAAGGCUACAGUAGCACUCCAUUAUAUCCUUAUAGCCAUACCUACCCCUCUUACCUAUUUUUCACACUGCUGCAAGAGUGAUCUUUGGGAAAUGCAAAUCUUCUAUUACUCCUUUGCUUAAAAACCCUUCAGUAACUCCCCCUUGAACUUAGGGUGAAGAUCAAACUCCUUGCUAUGGGCUAUGAUGGCCACACAGUCUGUCUCCAGCCUACCUCUCCAGCCUUAUCUCUCAUGACUUCUUUCUGUUCCACAAAUGUGGAAAGCUUUGCUUUAGAGCUUUGCACAUACCUUUCCUCUCUGCCUGUUUCCUCCAAAUUAUCUUUGACACUUAUUCCUGGUUAACUUCUACCUAUCCUACAGGUUUCAUCUUAGAAUUAAUUUUCUCAGGGAGUUGUCCUUUGACCCCUGACGUGGAUGUGCUCUCUGUCCUUUGUCUUCAUAGUACCCUCACAUUUGUAAUAUAUGAGUAUUUGUAAAAUUAUUUGUUUAAUGUUUGUUUCCCCUUUUAGACUCUAGAACUGUAAUAAGGGACUUACUGUUUUACUCCCUGCUGUAUCCCUUCUCCUGUGUAGUGCCUGGUGUAUAUUUGCAUUGAAUAAUUAGUAGAAAAAUCUAAUAAAAGUGGUACCAUGAUCAGACUGGGUGAGCCACUUAGCAGCAGGAACCUGUAUGGGAGAGAGUGUUCUCACUCCUGGAGGGGCUCGGGUAAAGUUGGGAUGGGCUUACCAUGAAAUGUAAAGUAGUGGAGGAAGUGGAAGGACCUACUGCUAUGAGAAUGCCUGCCUUCCUGUGUCUGACCCUUUGUCACAGCUAUUUAGGACUCCUUUCUGGUUGUCUGACUCCUUAUUUUGCCCUCAUCCAAAAACUGUAGGGUAUUUUUCUUCCUGUUGAAUUGUUGUUUCUAGAAUUCACUGGACAUAUAAACCUCAUAUCCUUUGGGAUUGGUUAUAGGCCAUAGAUUGCCAGAACUGAAAGAGUCACUACUGCUAUUACUGGUUUGUGUAAUUAUCAGCUUACAGUUAGUGCUUGCAUGUGCCAGGCAUUGUUAUAUAAUUAUCUCCAUUUUACAGAUGAGGCAGCCAGGUCAUAAGAGACUAAUGAAUUUUCCCAAGUAAUUUUAUAUAUAAUCUGGUCCAACCCUCUUAAGUAAAAGUGAGGAAAUCAAGGCCUAGAAAUAUUAACUACUUACCAGUAACACCAAGUGUGUUAGUUUCCCAAGGCUGCCAUAACAAAACAGCAAACUGGGUGGCUUAAAACAAUAGAAAUUUGUCUCAGUUCUGGAGACUAGAUGGCUGAAAGUAUUGGCACGGCCAUGUUCUCUGAAACUUGUAGGAAUGAAAGAAUUCUUCCUUGCCUCUUCCUAGCUUUUGCUGGUUUGUGGGCUGUUUUUGAUAUUCCUUGGCUUGCAGCUUCAUAACUCCAAUCUCUGUCUUCAUUGUCACAAGGAGUUCUCUCUGUUUUUCUAUCUUUACAUGGCCAUCUUAUAAGGACACUAGUUAUAUUGGAUUAGGGGCCCACCCUACUUCAGUAUGACUUCAUCUUAACUAAUUAUUAAAAAUGGCAAAAACCAUAAUUACUUUUGCACCAAACUAAUACAUCUGUAAUGACACUAUUUCCAGGUCAUAUUCUUGAGAUACUGGGGGUUAGGACUUCAACAUGUCAUUCUUUGGGGGACACGAUUCAACUCAUAGCACUAAGUAAUUAAUGGAAGAGCUGGCAUAAGAAUGCAAAUAGAUUCAUCAAUGAGAUAAUUUUUACGUUGUGCCCCAUAUGAGUUCAUAUUCUUGUAAUGUGUUUAUUCCACAUUCAUUGGAUAUAACUCAAAGUUUUAGUCAAACCUCUUUCUCUUUAGCCAUAGAGCAAUUUUGAGAUUUAUAUUUUAUUGUCUUAUUUGUGGUUGACUGUUACCAAUUUUAUUUUUUAACAGCUUUAUUGAGUCAUAAUUGUCAAACAAAAAAUUGCACCUAUUUAAAGUGUACAACUUGAUACCUUUUGGCACAUAUAUACACUUACGAAACCAUCCCCACAAUAAAGAUAGUAAGCAUAUCCAUCACGCCAAAA